AGGCAGAGGUUGCAGUGAGCUGAGAUCGUGCCACUGCGCUCCAGCCUGGGUGACAAAGAUAAACUCCAUCUGAACAAAAAAGAAAAAGAAAAGCUAAGCAUGGACUUAAUUUCUCUGAGAUUUAAAGCUGCAAAGAGUUGCUCUUCAUGAAGUAGAUGGGAUCUCAGCUGGGCAGUGAAAUGUGAGUGGGGUUUGGUCAGCUGGUGGAGGUUGCAGGAAAAUUAUUUACAUAGGUGAAGAGUAAGCGCAAUCAGGUAUCUAGGAAAGAAUGAGGGGUUCAGAGUAUACGAAACCAAUUUGAGCUAUAACACAAGGAGGGUAGGAUUCAUGUAGAAGAGUUGUAGGAAAUAUUGCUGAUGUAAUAUUUUGUACUCAAACAGUUCUGUGGAUUGGUGACAGAUUUUUUUUUUCAGGUAAGUAAACUAUUACCCCUGGAUAUUCAUCUUUCUGUGUAGCUGGUUGAGAAACAGGGGAGUAACAGUAAAGAAACUGUUUUAGAAUAAAUCUGGUGACAGCAGAAGAGAAUAUGAGACACAUUGUGCUCACAGAGCCUAGAAGAGUGUGACAGUAGUUGAGGGCACCGCUGUUGUCUUAGAGUGAAGUGAGGAGAACCUACAUUGGUGUGGUAGUCAUGGGAGUGGAAGGAGGAAUGAAAUGUGAAAGCCCAUUGGAGGCAGAAUCAAAAUGCCUUGGUCUUAAUAGUCAACUAUUAAGGAGAAAUUAUUGGCUGACUUAGGAAGAAGUGAAAAAUGUGAAAUACCAAUAAAACACCAGGCUUGUGAUUUUAGUCAGGGUAAAGCUUAAGCAUUGUGUGAUUCUAGAUAGAUUACUGAGGAGUUUUGUUCCAUUUAUUUUAUGUCCAUAUCUUUGAGCUAUGAUUCUAUCCUUUAUUUCUUGACAUACCCAAACAUUUUUUAAACUAUUGUGAUACAGCUUUUAUAUGAUAAGUCUCACUCUUUGAAGUGUACAGUUUGGUGGUUUUUAGUAUAUUCAGAGUUAUGCAGCCAUUACCACUACCUAAUUUCAGAACCUUUUCUUCUCCCCAGAAAGAAACCCCAUGCCCAUUAGCAGUCACUCUGUAUACUCGUCUCCCCCACCGUUGAUCCUGGCGACCUCUGAUCUAAUUUCUGUCUCUGUAGAUUUGCCUAUCCUGGACAUUUCAUAUAAAUAGAAUCAUACAAAAUGUGGCAUUUUGUAAUUGACUUUUCUUUGAAGUGAUUAUAAAGCAAAUGCCUGAAGAGGCCAAGCUUAGGAUAGUGUUUGCUGUACAGCUUUGACAACUGAAUUUUUUUUAAGUUGAAAAUAUUACUGUGUCUGUAUAUGUGGCAUAUUAUCCUUAGAUGACCGUUACUUCAAUUAUUAGAAUUUUUUUCCCUAGUAUUCUUGAACUGUCUCAAUAUUCAGUAGGAACCCUUUGGAGACAAAGAGCAGUAAGAAUUUGGAACACAUAUUGACGAAAUGAAUGUCAUUUAAUACAGUAGUAGAGUCGACCACUUUUAGGUGUCAGUGCUGCUGGAAGUGUAUAUUAAGGAAAAGUUUACUUAUCUUACUUAUGUAGUGAAGGUACUAGAACUACUUCUGUCUUCUGUUUAGAUUUCAACAAACAUUUGCAUAGGUAUUAUGCAGUUGUACAAAUGUACUGUCUUUUGACCUGAAAAUGCAAAAACUUUCUUCCUACUUUCUGAGACUCUGCAACCUUAAAGGAAGAGUGGGGUACUUUAAAGGAAAGGUGGUGUUGGUUGGAUAAUGGGUGACAAUGUCUGCCAUAUACUUCCUUUUCCCAAAACAAGUUCCUGUCUACCAUCAGCAUCUCCAAAAUUUGAAGAUCAAGUGUGGUGUUAACUCAUUAACUAAAUGACUAGACUUUGAGCAGUUGUGGAACCAAAAUCUGAGUGAGUGCCUGGAUGUUCUAAUUCUGUUAAAUCAAUGAGUGCACAUUAUAUACAAUACUCUCUUAGCCCAGUGGCAGAUUUAAGGAGUGAGAGAGAGAUUUCAAAUGUUUCAGAAAUCAAAUACACAAAGAAUAAAAAUUUGUAAUCCCAUGAUUCUUUACCUGAGUUUAAUUUUUCGGAGAGUUUUUCUUUUAGAUUUUCUUUUCCUUCCAUUAAACUUUCACUUUGAAAGCUCCCAGGGUUUGGGCAAAGCAAGUGGGAAAGACACUUGCUUGGAUUCUCCAGGGCAAGGGAGUUAAAGAGGGCUUCUUUCCCUCAUUUUAUUAUUGAAUAAUGUCAUGAAAACAAUUAUUAAGGUGAAUGGUCUACAGUAGAAGUUUUUAGAUGCCUUCUCUGCAAAAUAAUUUGGUUUAGUCAAUGCAAGGAUGCCUUUGGUUAGCUGGAAUGGAAGAUGCGCAGGCUAGAGUGGUCUUGGCAAGUCUUCUGGGGGGAAAUACAGCAUUUGGAAGGGUAGGAAGCAGAAGGAAUCUCAAGCAAGGGAAAGGUGUGGGCAGAGCCCCGGAGGACAGAACCGUUUGUGGUGGACUUGGUGUCCACAUAGAUCUAAUCAGUGGUCUUAGCUUUUGUGCUUUCAAAAUUACCACAGUUUUUGUUCUAAAACUAUCAUUCCCUUGAUUUUACUUUAGGCAUGCUAUCUGUGUAUUUUGAAAUUUAAAAUAACAUUAAAGGAGAAAUGAAAUUAUUUUGUUUGAGAAAGAAUUAAAAGGUUAAAACAUCUUGAUCUAAAUAAUUUUCUAAUGGGAGAUUUGGUACAUCCCCAGAAGUUGUCUUUGGUUCAGAGAACAGUCUUCAGACCUAGAAAGGACUUGAGGAGUCCCAGAGAGGAGCCACAUGGUGUGAACCAUUCGAUUCUCACAACAGAAUGGAUAAGAACAAUUUCAACCAUGAAACCGUGCAGAUGUUCAUAUUUUGAAUAGGCUCCUACUUUCAAGAAUGAAAAAGGUAUCCCAGCAGUUUGGGAGGCUGAGGCAGGCGGAUCACGAGGUCAAGAGAUCGAGACCAUCCUGGCUAACACGGGCUGAAGCAGUGCCUACUCGAUAGAAUCAGUCAUCAUGCAAAUAAAAGCCACCUGAGUCAAAGGCAAAGCCAGAGUGCAGCUUGGAGCAAAGAAGUUAAAAGCAUAUUGGCAGAGGAAGAGCCCUGGCAUUCCAGCAGGAGCUAACAGGAAAAAGAAAAUCAAUGGCAGUAGCCCUGACACAUUCACUUCUGGUGGUUACCACUCACCUGGGGAUGUGAGUCUCGGCGGGCCAGGCUCCUGGGGACAGGGAGCCCAAGGGGCAGUAGAGGGUAAUUGUUAAGAUUGUAGAUGGACUGUUGGGUACUGGUUAAGAAUUCUGGAUUUGAAUCCUGCCUCUCCGUCUGCUAAGAAUUGAUUAGGGAUUGAUUAGCAUAUGAUUUAGGGCAAGUUGCUUGAGGUCUUUGGGCCUCUCUUUUCACAUCUGUAUAAUAGAGGUGGUAUUUUUUGACUUCCAUUUGUGAAGUUUAAAUGAGAUUCGUUAUUGUUGCUUUUAUGUGAAUCCUUAGUACAUGGCCUGCUGCAAACACCCAGGACACCGAGGAAAUGGUCGUUGCUGUUUGAUUUUCCUCAUCCCCAGUCUCAAGGGGAAGCCAGGCCAAUGAGAAGAGCCACUUGCCAUCAGGCUGUCCCUUUAGGAGUCACUGAAAGGGCCCCAGGGUGGGAUGGUGGGGAGAUAAGAACCACGAGAGAAGUUGGCACAAAGGAGUUAUGGGAAAAAGGUUCCAAGAUAGGCAGAAAAGAAGCUUUUGCCAGUUGAUGGGGGAAGAAAGGAAGUCAGAGGGCUUAGACAGUGAGGGGGGACAGAACAUCUCCAUGUGCACUCUCAUCUCUUGGAGUCAGCAACAGGUAUCUACGGGGAGGGCCGUGCAUCCUCUACUACCCUGCAGGAUCUGGAGGUAAGAGGCCCUGGGCCGAGGUGCAGUGACCCUGCAGGCCAGCCCUCCAACCUCCUCCCACAGCAGGGGCUUGUUGCCCCUCUGCCAGCUGAGGCAGCCCACACACCCCCACCAGCCCUAAUGAUUAUUCUCUCUACCCCUCCCCACAAUCUUUCUCCAACUCCUUCUCUCUGCAUGCACCUCAGAGCCAGUACCAAGAACUAGCAGUAGCCCUGGAUUCAAGCUCCGCAAUAAUCAGUCAACUCACUGAAAACAUCAAUUCACUGGUUCGCACAUCUAAGGAGGAGAAGAAGCAUGAGAUACAUCUGGUACAGAAGCUUGGGAGGAGCUUGUUCAAACUCAAAAACCAGACGGCUGAACCCCUGGCCCCACAGCCCCCAGCAGGGCCAUCUAAGAUGGAGCAGCUACAAGAUGAGACCAACCACCUAAGGAAGGAGCUAGAGAGUGUGGGAAGACAGCUCCAGGCUGAGGUGGAAAACAAUCAGAUGUUGAGUCUCCUGAACAGGAGACAGGAGGAGAGGCUACGUGAACAGGAGGAGAGGCUACGUGAACAGGAGGAGAGGCUGUGUGAACAGGAGGAGAGGCUGUGUGAACAGGAGGAGAGGCUACGUGAACAGGAGGAGAGGCUGUGUGAACAGGAGAAGCUGCCAGGGCAGGAGAGGCUGCUGGAAGAGGUGGAGAAGCUGUUAGAACAGGAGAGGCGGCAGGAGGAGCAGGAGAGGCUGCUGGAGAGGGAGAGGCUGCUGGACGAGGUGGAGGAGCUCCUGGAGCAGGAGAGGCUUCGGCAACAGGAUGAGAGGCUGUGGCAGCAGGAGACUCUGCGGGAGCUGGAGAGGCUGCGGGAGCUGGAGAGGAUGCUGGAGCUGGGGUGGGAAGCCCUGUACGAGCAGCGGGCCGAGCCACGCAGCGGCUUCGAGGAGCUGAACAACGAGAACAAGAGCACACUGCAGUUGGAGCAGCAAGUAAAGGAGCUGGAGAAGUCGGGUGGAGCUGAAGAGCCAAGAGGCUCCGAGUCUGCAGCAGCAGCCAGACCAGUAGCUGGAGCCCCAGUCCCACAAGGAGCUUGGAUGUGCGGACAAGCAGGGUGGACUCCCCAGGAGCACCCAGGCUUGAGUGGAGAAGCUGUUGGUACAGGAGAGGCGGCAGGAGGAGCAGGAGAGGCUGCAUGCCAUUCUUUUCGGGCUGCCGAGAACAGGGAGCUAAACAUCACCAUCAUCUAAGAGCGGGUCAAGAAAUUGAAAAAAAAAAACAAAACAUUUAAGGGGUUAAUAUCCUACACAAUUCAUUUACUUCAUUUGAAUGUUAGAGCCACUUAUGUUUGUGUUUCUAAUUUAUAGUUUAAAUUUAUUUGUGUUUCUAAUUUAUAGUUUAAAUUUAUUUGUUUCUAAUUUAUAGUUUAAAUUUAUUUGUGUUUCUAAUUUAUAGUUUAAAUUUAUUUUUGUUUCUAAUUUAUAAUUUAAAUUUAUUUGUAAAAAGUUAAAUGAGAGUGGGUCUUUCUCUCAUGUUCACUCUGGCAUCUUUUAGCAUUUCUUUAAUUUGAUAAUUAUAGGACGUUAGCAUGCAUAUCGAGUUUGCCCUUAUGUGGUGGGAGUUCAAACACACAAAGACCCACUGUAUGCACACAACUGUUCUUGCUGGUUUGGGAUAGGCUGCCAUGCUUUUUUAAUGUUAGUACAGCCUGUAUAUUCAUUACGGAAUUCAGAUAAAAUUUCCUUAUGUUCUGCUGUUAUGUUUGAUCGAAUCCUAAUCACAGUGAGCUCUUCAUUAGCUCAAUAUGUGGUUUGCCCUCUGGAAACAGCCUUUCCCCCUUUUUCUGUGUAUUGGGGAUGGGAGUAAUAACAUUUUGGGGAGGUUUUUAAAUCUCCCAGAAGAGGAAAGUGGCCUGCUUUGGCAGGUGUGUGCAGGAUAGAAUAUGUUUCAUUUGUUCCGGUGCCAAGAAUGAGCGCUGUACUACGGUAGUUCCCUUAGGAUUUGUAUGUGCUCUAGGCUCAUGAAGAUACUGCCUCAUGAGCUGUGGCAGUUGUACUCUUUUUUGAUGACCUGAAAAGGGAUUAUUUCUGAGGAAUGAAAGGCUCCCAUCAUGACUGUGGAUGUGGAAAACCUUUUCUAGCUGAGAGCAUUUAUAUCUACAAUACAUUUUAAAGUCAGAGUUCAUGUUCCCUGUUUUAAUCACAUGACUACAUGUCCCAGUACACAAAAGGGCACUGGUUGGCGUUCUCCUUAAUGUAUUUAGUAAAGAUCAGAAGAAAUCCUUUAAGAGUUUAAAUGCCCCUGGAACAGGCAUAUACAGGCUCUAGUCAAGAAUGAAUUCGAGUGAAGGAAAGCUGUGUGACACCUGGCAUUCCUCUGUGUUCAUGGAGCUUAUUUGAGGCUAGAAGAUGGAUUUUACCAUCUAGACCUCUCUGGCUAAUAGCUAGUCUUCAACCAUCUGACAUAGGAAUUUACUUCUUUUCCUUGAAUGGAGAACACUUUAAAAAUAAUAACAAACAUUAUUAUAAACUAAUAUAUGUGAGAGUACUUAGUUGAAACAAAAAGGAGUUUUAGUAGACAGUAUUAUACUACAUUUGAAAAUCAAGGAGCAGUUUAUGCAACGUAAAACGUUUACAAACUGCAGCACAAUCUACUGUUCGUGAAUGUCAAAGUGUCAUGAGGAAAGUGUCUAUACAAUCACAGAGUUAUAUUUCCUCACAAAGUUCUUUACAAAGAGUGAAAUAUGUUUUUAUACCUCUCAGUUUCAGUUAGAGGCAUAUUUUGUGUAAUAUUUAUGGCUUAAAAUGGACUAAAGGUCCUGUUCUUGCCUUGUCUGAACUUGCCGCUUUUGCAUUCUUUGAGUUCAGUUUAAAGACAGUUACUUUAAGCCCAUUUUAAACCCUCAGGCUAGAAAUCGUACCACUGUUAAUUAGCCACAUUAUUUGGUCUAACAGUUUAUCAUUCUGAAACUGAGCUUACCUAAUACAUUGAUAAAUUAUUUCAAAGGUAUUUUUAUAGUUCAAAUCGCUUCACUUUUACCCUGACACGUAUAAAUGACUAGGAAUGACCUUCAGAUAGCAUUUAGCAACUGUAACCAAUCUGACAAUAAUGUGUUCAUCAGGUACCUGUGGAUUAAAUCACAUACUGGCAUAUUUAAGCUGAAUGUCAGUCUGAAAAAUAAAUGUACUAUAUUAACUCAAAUACCACUCUCUGUGUAGGUAUUUUGUCAUAUGUUUAAGAAAAAGCUAAAGAGAAUGGAAAUCCUAUGACAAUAACUAUGACAAUAACUAUGACAAGUCUUUCUUCAAAGUGCAUGCAGUCUUUUGCAGUACCUCAUUCAGCCAAGUAUUUGUUCUCUACCUCAUUCAGUAUAAGGCAGCCUUUAAUUUGCUUAGAAGGCAACAUUAGAAGGUUAGAGUUCAGCAGGAACAUAGAAUUUUAAAAUGUGACUUCAACUGAAUAAAUUUGAAUUUCUGUAGGGAGUAAAGAAUCAAAACACCUAUUUAAAGACUGCAAAAUAUGAUAAUUAUUUUUAAAGUAAUUGAUUAAACCUGGUAGGUUUUCCCAAAAUGAAAAACAAUCAGUUCUAAAACCAAAGCUGAUUUUUAGAAAAUGUGAAAAUGUAAAUCAACCCUAUCCAUAAUAGAUUCUCUAAAACUUUAUCUUACAGUCACUUUCAAAUAACUAUUCAAAAAUGUAACUGCUAUAUUAACGUCUUAAAAUAAUUUAAAACAUUUUAAAAUAUGAAUACUGUAGUUUAAAACAAAGAAUCUAGGGGAAGGAAAAGUAGACAAAGAAAUGCCAAUUCCAGUCCAAAGCUGUAUUUGCCAAGUUUUCUUAGAAUGACUUUUACCGAUUUAUGAAUUCUUAUACACAGAAUGCAUAAUGGAAAUACUGAUUUUUGUCUAAAGUGGCAUUAUUGACUGCUGCUGUGAUGCUACUAUAAUGUAAUACAUUAUUAAAUUGUUUCAAGGUGCUGUUUUGCCUAAAAA